AGCGCGCGCAGGGGCUGCGGAGCGGCAGGAUGCAGGAGGAGCUGGCGUGGGAGACCGACGGCCUGCUUCCUCUGGAGAGGCAGCUCCACGAGGCCGCCCGCCAGAACAAUGUCGGCAGGAUGCAGGAGCUGAUUGGGAGGAGGGUUAACACCAGGGCCAGAAACCACGUGGGCAGGGUGGCCCUGCACUGGGCUGCAGGUGCAGGGCACGAGCAGGCUGUGCGUCUGCUUCUGGAGCACGAGGCUGCUGUGGACGAGGAGGAUGCGGUAGGGGCCCUCACAGAGGCACGUCUGUGUUUUGGGAUGAAUGCGCUUCUCCUGUCUGCCUGGUUCGGCCACUUACGAAUCCUCCAGAUCUUGGUAAACUCAGGGGCCAAGAUCCACUGUGAGAGCAAGGAUGGCCUGACCUUACUGCACUGCGCAGCCCAAAAAGGCCAUGUGCCUGUGCUGGCGUUCAUAAUGGAGGACCUGGAGGAUGUGGCCCUGGACCACGUAGACAAGCUGGGGAGGACGGCGUUUCACAGGGCAGCUGAGCACGGGCAGCUGGAUGCUCUGGACUUCCUCGUGGGCUCUGGCUGUGACCACAAUGUCAAAGACAAGGAGGGGAACACUGCCCUUCAUCUGGCUGCUGGUCGGGGCCAUAUGGCUGUGCUGCAGCGACUUGUGGACAUCGGGCUGGACCUGGAGGAGCAGAAUGCGGAAGGUCUGACUGCCCUGCAUUCGGCUGCUGGAGGAUCCCACCCUGACUGUGUGCAGCUCCUCCUCAGGGCUGGGAGCACCGUGAAUGCCCUCACCCAGAAAAACCUAAGCUGCCUUCACUAUGCAGCCCUCAGUGGCUCGGAGGAUGUGUCUCGGGUCCUCAUCCACGCAGGAGGCUGCGCCAACGUGGUUGAUCAUCAGGGUGCCUCUCCUCUGCACCUCGCUGUGAGGCACAACUUCCCUGCCUUGGUCCGGCUCCUCAUCAACUCCGACAGUGACGUGAAUGCCGUGGACAAUAGGCAGCAGACGCCCCUUCACCUGGCUGCAGAGCACGCCUGGCAGGACAUAGCAGAUAUGCUCCUCAUUGCUGGGGUUGACUUAAACCUGAGAGAUAAGCAGGGAAAAACCGCCCUGGCAGUGGCCGUCCGCAGCAACCAUGUCAGCCUGGUGGACAUGAUCAUAAAAGCUGAUCGUUUCUACAGAUGGGAGAAGGACCACCCCAGUGAUCCCUCUGGGAAGAGCUUGUCCUUUAAGCAGGACCAUCGGCAGGAAACACAGCAGCUCCGUUCUGUGCUGUGGCGGCUGGCCUCCAGGUAUCUGCAGCCCCGUGAGUGGAAGAAGCUGGCAUAUUCCUGGGAGUUCACGGAGGCACAUGUCGACGCCAUCGAGCAACAGUGGACAGGCACCAGGAGCUAUCAGGAGCACGGCCACCGAAUGCUGCUCAUUUGGCUGCAUGGCGUGGCCACGGCUGGUGAGAACCCCAGCAAAGCGCUGUUCGAGGGCCUCGUGGCCAUUGGCAGGAGGGACCUGGCUGGCUGGAGUACAAUGGCGAGAUCUCAGCUCACGGCAACCUCCGCCUCCCGGGUUCAAAUGAUUCUUGUGCCUCAGCCUCCCGAGUAGCUGGGAUUACAGGUGCAUGCCAUCACAGCUGGCUAAUUUUUGUAUUUUUAGUAGAGAUGGGGUUUGGCCAUGAUGGCCAGGCUGGAAAAUUGAAACAUAAUUUCACAAUUAUUCCUUUUUCCACCUUAAAUAAUAAGAGUAGAAUACUUUCUGUGUUUUUAUCUUAUACACAUGAAUAAAUGCUAUGGCUUAUCACAGUUACAAUGUGUUUUCUGAAAGUAAAGAUUAUUUUACCUUGAAAUUACAAAAAUUAUUUUCAGUUUUCCAAAAUUCUAUCUUUAAACCUAAAUAAUUCAAUUUCAUGGAUGCACAAAUGUUUAUUGAGAGUCUCAUAUUCAUGCUUUUCUUCACAGCACUAUAAAGUUGGACUUGGAAAAUUUGGACAGCCAUUUGCCAUUGUAAUUUUUAUUCUUUUUUCUCCUGAUUAUUUGACAAAACUUGUAUCCACAUUGUAGCUGUUCAUGUGUCUGCUUCUAUUGCAUAUUGUAAAAUUAUUAACUACUUCCCAAAAUAGUAUUUCUCUCAGCAGAUAUUUCUUUGGUACUACCAUGUAUUGUGUAACUUUUGGGAAAGUAAGGUGGCUUCCCUGCUCUCAGUGAAGCAUUUUAUUAAAAGAAUAAUUAUAAUUAAAAAAACACGAUACAGAUCAGUGCAUAUAGUAUAUUACUAAUAGUAUGCUGUUAAUUGUGUAAGAAAGAAAGGAAAUUAGAAAACAUAUUUGCAUAAAUAAAAGCUAGACAAAGGCUAAGAAACUAAUCAGGUGGUUUCCCUGGGGUAGUAGGAUAAUGGGGAACAGUGGGGCUGGGACCGGGUGGGAGAAAGAGUUCUCAGUGGUUCCUUUCUAUACAGUUUUAACUUUUGAAAUGUGUGAGAGUGUUACUUACUGAAAACUGAAAGGAUAUGACAUGCUGGAACAGGCAAAACUACAAAGACAGUAAAAAGAUCAGUGAUUUCCAGGAGCUGCAAGGGCAGUGAGAGGAAGGGAGGGAUGAGGAGGUGGAGCGCAGGGGAUGUUAGGGCAGUGAAAGGUUCUGUAUGACACUGUGAUGGUGGGUACAUGACAUUGGGCAUUGGUCAAAACCCAUAGCAUGUACAGCACAAAGCGUUUGCUCUAAUGUGAGCUAUGGACUUUAGUUAAUAGUAACGUGUCAAUAUUGGUUCAUCAGUUGUAUCAAAUGUACCACACUGAUGCCAGAUGUUAAUAAUCGGGGAAACUGUGUGUGCUGAAGAGUACGUGGGAGCUCUCUGUGCUAUCUGCUCAAUUUUUCUCUAAACCUAAAACUGUUCUAAAAUAGAAAGUCUGUGAAAAAAAACAAAAGUAAAGUUAUAAAAGGAAAAGAAAACAGAGGCUUUAAAUUAAAUCAUCUAUUCCUUGGGAAAGGUAUUUUGUACCAUAUGGGACUGAAAUCAUUUAUCUGGAUGAAUUUUAUAAAAUGAAUUUUGUAAUUUUUUUCUGAGAAAAAAAAGUUCUUAAAUACAAUAAAAUUGAAAUGUUGAAAUAUA